GACGGCGGCGAGGAGGAGGCCGCGGCGCGGGACGCAUAGAGCUGCGGCUCGGGCGGCGCCUCCCUGCGGCGGCCCGGCCCGGCUCCGGCCCCCGCUGGGGCAAUGCUCCCCGGGGCCGCGGGAUGAGCCAGGUGAGCGCGGAGACCCCCAGCACUCCCUGCCUGGUGCGCAUGGACGGGGGUGGGGAGGCGGGGCGGGAAGCGGCGUCCUCGGCCUCUGUUCCCCGGGGCUGUGUGACCUUGGGCGGCCCCGCACCCUCUCUGGGCCCAGAGCCCCAGCACCGGCAGGGCCUGCGGAGGCCGCUCUGAGUCCUGGCCCCGCAGGCACCGGCCUGGAGCGCUGGGGAGGCUUCUUGGAGGAGGCGGGGCCUGGCCCUGGCCCCGGAUCGCCGAGACCGGCCACGCUGCGCCGCCUGGACGCCGGGCUCCUCCACCCACAGCUCUGCGACCUUCACGAGCUCGACCCUUUCUGCGCCUCAGUUUCCUCAUCUAUAAAAUGGAGAUAAUGCCUCCGCGCGCUGAGCCCGAGCGCGGUCGUGCUGUUACACUAUUGCUGCUGCUAUGUCGUUAAUGACGGCACAGCCCUUAUGGAAGGGGGGCCAAGGAAGGCACGGGGACCUUCCCGCAGGACAUGGGGUGGGCACCAGCCCUAAGCCAUGCACAUAACCCACUCUGAGGUCAGGACCUGGGUUCCUUUCGUGUCCACUGGGGGCCUUAGCCGUUGUCUUCACUUCUCUAGGUCCCAGCCCUUCACAAUGGGCGCGCCUCCCUGCCUGAGAGGGAGGCCCCAGCCAAGCCCCAGUUUCCACCGCAAAAAGCCACACAGCAAACACUUAAUGGACCCUAAAUUUAUAAAAAUUAUCCCAUAGAGUCCUAUGAGGCAGGGAAUGUUACUGUACCCAUUUCGCAGAUGAGGAAACUUGGGGCACCGACAUUUCCCAGAGCCAACAUGUAAACCAGGCAUUUGGCCUGAGUGACAGACUGGUGCAGGUGGCCAGCAGCUUAAUUUGUACUGAGCGCUUACUGGGUCCCCACAGCGAUCCUGAACUGUGUUCCUGCCCACAGUGACUCGGCCGGUCCGGGCAUGGCAGACCCAGUGGCGGGCAUCGCGGGCUCGGCGGCCAAGAGCGUGCGGCCAUUUCGCUCCAGUGAGGCCUACGUGGAGGCCAUGAAGGAGGACCUGGCCGAGUGGCUCAAUGCCUUGUACGGCCUGGGUCUCCCGGGUGGUGGCGAUGGCUUCCUGACAGGGCUGGCCACGGGCACGACCCUGUGCCAACAUGCCAACGCCGUGACCGAGGCUGCCCGUGCAUUGGCAGCCGCCCGCCCGGCCCGAGGUGUGGCCUUCCAGGCGCACAGUGUAGUGCCUGGCUCCUUCAUGGCGCGCGACAACGUGGCCACCUUCAUCGGCUGGUGCCGCGUGGAGCUGGGUGUGCCGGAGGUGCUCAUGUUUGAGACUGAGGACCUGGUGCUGCGCAAGAACGAGAAGAGCGUGGUGCUGUGCCUGCUGGAGGUGGCGCGGCGUGGGGCACGCCUGGGCCUGCUGGCCCCACGCCUCGUGCAGUUUGAGCAGGAGAUUGAGCGGGAGCUGCGUGCUGCACCCCCAGCCCCCAACGCCCCUGCCGCUGGGGAGGACACCACUGAAACCGCCCCCGCACCAGGGACUCCUGCCCGCGGCCCCCGCAUGACACCCAGCGACCUGCGCAACCUCGACGAGCUGGUGAGGGAGAUUCUGGGCCGCUGCACCUGCCCUGACCAGUUUCCCAUGAUCAAGGUCUCAGAGGGGAAGUACCGUGUGGGGGACUCGAGCCUGCUCAUCUUUGUGCGGGUGCUGAGGAGCCACGUGAUGGUGCGAGUGGGUGGUGGCUGGGACACGCUGGAGCAUUACCUGGACAAGCACGACCCGUGCCGCUGCUCCUCCACUGCUCAUCGCCCACCCCAGCCGAGGGUCUGCACCUUUUCUCCACAGAGGGUGUCGCCCACCACCAGUCCCCGCCCUGCUAGCCCAGUCCCUGGGAGUGAGCGCCGGGGCUCCCGGCCUGAGAUGACUCCCGUUAGCUUACGAAGCACAAAGGAGGGGCCCGAGACCCCACCCAGGCCCCGGGAUCAGCUGCCCCCCCAUCCCCGCUCCCGCCGCUACUCCGGGGACAGUGACUCCUCAGCCUCCUCCGCCCAGAGCGGCCCCCUUGGUACCCGCAGUGAUGACACAGGCACUGGCCCCCGGAGGGAGCGACCCAGCCGGCGGCUGACCACAGGCACCCCGGCCUCUCCGAGACGGCCUCCUGCCCUGCGCAGCCAGUCCCGAGACCGGCUGGAUCGCGGCCGGCCCCGGGGGGCCCCAGGAGGCAGGGGAGCCCAGCUGUCGGUCCCCAGCCCUGCCCGGCGGGCCCGGAGCCAGAGCCGCGAGGAGCAGGCUGUGCUGCUUGUGCGCAGGGAUCGAGACGGGCAGCACUCAUGGGUGCCAAGGGGCAGGGGCAGUGGGGGCUCGGGCAGGAGCACCCCCCAGACUCCCCGUGCCCGCAGCCCUGCAGCACCCCGGCUUUCCCGGGUCUCCAGCCCCAGUCCAGAGUUGGGCACCACACCGGCCAGCAUCUUCCGCACACCCCUGCAGCUCGACCCGCAGCAGGAGCAGCAGCUGUUCCGGCGCCUGGAAGAGGAGUUCCUGGCCAAUGCCCGGGCCCUUGAGGCUGUUGCUAGCGUGACCCCCACUGGACCAGCCCCUGACCCAGCUCGGGCCCCCGACCCUCCAGCUCCUGACUCUGCCUAUUGUUCCUCCAGUUCCUCCUCUUCGUCCCUCAGCGUCCUGGGUGGCAAAUGUGGCCAACCUGGGGACUCUGGCCGGACGGCCAAUGGGCUGCCUGGGCCCCGAAGCCAAGCCCUUUCCAGCUCCUCCGAUGAAGGCAGCCCCUGCCCUGGCAUGGGGGGGCCACUAGAUGCACCUGGGAGCCCCCUGGCUUGCACUGAACCCUCGAGGACCUGGGCACGGGGUCGGAUGGACACACAGCCAGACCGUAAACCCUCACGUAUCCCCACGCCUCGGGGCCCCCGCCGCCCCUCCGGACCCGCAGAGCUGGGGACAUGGCAUGCCCUGCACUCAGUCACCCCGAGGGCUGAGCCAGAUUCCUGGAUGUGAUGGACCAGCUCAGCUGUCCCCAGACCCCAUCCCUUCUCCUUUUCCUUUGUGGCCUUAACCCUUCUGCAUCAGGGAGCCCCCUCUGCCUCUUGAGUACCAGACCUCAUGGGACCAGACCCCUUGGGACCACAUGGCACAAUGGGACCUCUGUUGUACAUUCCGGUUGGGGGAUGAGCGUUGCUAUUUAAUUACUAAUAUUAUUGAAUGCCUUAGAGGAGGCCGGGCGAGCCCGGUGUUCUGAAGACCUGUGGCCCAGCAGAGCCUCUGACAGUAAAGUUUUGCUCCAGCCA